GAGCGCUCUCCAAACCACGGCUCCCGGCGCUCAGGCGGGCCGCUGCCAAGACCCGGCCUGGAGUCCCCGCAGAGUUGCGCGGCGCACGGACCCCGUGGCCUUGGGGCGUCAGGAGGCCCAACCCAGAUCUGCGCGCCCAGGCAGCGCUCAGGCCGCUAGAAUGGACCCCGGCAGCGGCGAGGAAGCGGAACUCUCUGCGGCUCCCUCUCCGCAGUGCGCCGGCAAGGUCCAGGUCCCAGCCUCCCCACCGCCGCCCGCGCCCUCCUAGGCCUCGGAGCGGCGCCUUUCUGCGGCCUCGAAGGUGGGGUGGGAAAGUUUGGGGAGUCCCGGCUCUCACAGCCUGUCGUGAGAACUGCCCCCGGGGAAUUCGUCCGCCGUACGGAAAAACUGGCCGGAGCAGAGUCGUCCGCGGUUCCGCGGUCGCGGGUGGAAGGUGAAGGUCGAGGGAGGUCAGGCUGCUUCUGCGUGUCCUGACGGCUGGCGUGUUCUCUUGAGAUGGGCUCGGGCUACUUGGCCAGCUUCAAUUUAAGCCACAGUGUCUCCGAGGCCCUGACCUGGUCCGGCCCGCCGACACUUGAGCCCCCAGAGCCUCAGAGAAGGCGAGGGGGUGGAUCUCCCAGUGCCGAGGCCCGCCGUCCUGGUCCAAGCCGGUCGCGGCACCGUGUCUGGGCACUGGAGCUGCUUCCAGCCCCGCGAACAGCUGGAGGGUGGCAGUGGGACCGCUCCGGCGGCUUCUCCCGCGCAGUGCCCCGCCUGGCCCCUUGUGAAGGGAGUGAGCGUCCCCUUUCCAGAGCUGUCCCCCGUGACAUCCAGAAAACGCGAAACCUCAGGAACAAGGUCGCAGCUUCAGACCGCGGCCCAGGAGGCCGAUGGUGGCCAGCGACGUGCCCCAGGACGGGCUGCUUCUGCACGGCCCCUUCGCACGCAAGCCCAAGCGGAUCCGCACGGCCUUCUCGCCCUCGCAGCUGCUGCGGCUGGAGCGCGCCUUCGAGAAGAACCACUACGUGGUGGGCGCCGAGCGGAAGCAGCUGGCCGGCAGUCUCAGCCUCUCCGAGACGCAGGUGAAGGUGUGGUUCCAGAACCGGAGGACAAAGUACAAACGGCAGAAGCUGGAGGAGGAAGGGCCUGAGUCCGAGCAGAAGAAGAAGGGCUCCCAUCACAUCAACCGGUGGCGCAUUGCCACGAAGCAGGCCAAUGGGGAGGACAUCGAUGUCACCUCCAAUGACUAGGGUGGGCAACCACAAACCCACGAGGGCAGAGUGCUGCUUGCUGCUGGCCAGGCCCCUGCGUGGGCCCAAGCUGGACUCUGGCCACUCCCUGGCCAGGCUUUGGGGAGGCCUGGAGUCAUGGCCCCACAGGGCUUGAAGCCCGGGGCCGCCAUUGACAGAGGGACAAGCAAUGGGCUGGCUGAGGCCUGGGACCACUUGGCCUUCUCCUCGGAGAGCCUGCCUGCCUGGGCGGGCCCGCCCGCCACCGCAGCCUCCCAGCUGCUCUCCGUGUCUCCAAUCUCCCUUUUGUUUUGAUGCAUUUCUGUUUUAAUUUAUUUUCCAGGCACCACUGUAGUUUAGUGAUCCCCAGUGUCCCCCUUCCCUAUGGGAAUAAUAAAAGUCUCUCUCUUAAUGACACGGGCAUCCAGCUCCAGCCCCAGAGCCUGGGGUGGUAGAUUCCGGCUCUGAGGGCCAGUGGGGGCUGGUAGAGCAAACGCGUUCAGGGCCUGGGAGCCUGGGGUGGGGUACUGGUGGAGGGGGUCAAGGGUAAUUCAUUAACUCCUCUCUUUUGUUGGGGGACCCUGGUCUCUACCUCCAGCUCCACAGCAGGAGAAACAGGCUAGACAUAGGGAAGGGCCAUCCUGUAUCUUGAGGGAGGACAGGCCCAGGUCUUUCUUAACGUAUUGAGAGGUGGGAAUCAGGCCCAGGUAGUUCAAUGGGAGAGGGAGAGUGCUUCCCUCUGCCUAGAGACUCUGGUGGCUUCUCCAGUUGAGGAGAAACCAGAGGAAAGGGGAGGAUUGGGGUCUGGGGGAGGGAACACCAUUCACAAAGGCUGACGGUUCCAGUCCGAAGUCGUGGGCCCACCAGGAUGCUCACCUGUCCUUGGAGAACCGCUGGGCAGGUUGAGACUGCAGAGACAGGGCUUAAGGCUGAGCCUGCAACCAGUCCCCAGUGACUC